AGGAGGGGAAGAUGAGAAACCAGCAGGUAUUACUUUUAAAAUAAAGAGUGUAUCUUAAAAAUAUAUACUUGAUAUCUGGUUCAAUUUGGUGUUUGAUAAAAAGGAGCUGGGCUCGGUGGCUCACACCUUUAAUCCCAGAACUUCGGGAGGCCAAGGCAGAUGGAUUGCUUGAGGUCAGGAGUUCAAGACCAGCCUGGCCAACAUGGUGAAACCUUGUCUACUAAAAUACAAAAAAAAAAAAAAAAUUAGCUAUGUGUGGUGGCAAGUGCCUAUAAUCCCAGCUACUAGGGAGGCUGAGGCAGGAGAAUUGCUUGAACCCAGGAGGCAGAGGUUGCAGUGAACUGAGACCAUGCCACUGCACUCCAGCCUGGACAACAGAGAGAGAAUCCGUCUCAAAAAAAAACAAAAAAAGGAAAAAAAUACACUUGAUAGAAAUAUAAGAGGAAUAUAUAUAGCCUACAGCUUAACAAAGAUUCCCCAUAUUUCCAAACAGAACAUGAUGGUAAAUUUAAGAUAUUUAGCAUUAUUUGGAAAAUACAUGGUUAGGUAAUCUUAAGGUAAUCUAUAUUUUUAUUUGAUGUUUUGUUAUAAUGUCAUUGUAAUAGCACUAAAACAUACUUACUGAGUAAUAUUUAAAAAUAAUUUCCUUUCUUUGAAUAAUCCAUCAAGUAGUAAAUUUUACAUUCAAUUAAGUGAAAAGGUAAAUGAGGAACAUCAGAAAUAAAAUAAAAUAGUGUUAGAGAAUUUUCCUUAAUUUAUGCCAAGUUUUGAAACAAAGAAUGAAAUCUCUGGAGAUUUUGGUUAUGCUAAGGGUCUAUCUAGUGGAAAUCAAGAUAGCUUUGAAUUUUGUCGUUUCCAAGAAAAUUUAAGUAUUGUAUGGUAUUUGAUAAUUUCUAAUUUUUUUCUUAUGAAGAAAAGAACCUAAAUUUCCAUAAUCUAAUUCAAUCCCUUUUAAAAAAUCAAUCAUAAACUGGGUUUCCACAUAUAUUUUUUAAAAUCUCUUUUACAGUGACACAAUUAAGAUGCAAAUUAUUUAGAUUUGCUCAAGUUUGCUUGUUCUUGUUCUUCCAAGUUCUAGGUCAAAUCCAAAGUUAAAAUACAUGAAAGCUUUUGAUUUAUGAAGUAGACAAUUUUGCCUUCAAAAUUACACCACAUGACCUCUUCUUAUUUGAGGAAUAUUUUCUUUUUCCCUAGGGAAAAAAAUUAUCCUAACCCCAAAAUGAUAGUGUACCUCUAUACCUGUAACAGCAACUGGCAUAUCUGUGCUCAAUUAUGUUUGUUAAAUGAAUGGUCCUUGUUAAGUACGAUAUAAGCAAAUAUCAACCUUCUUUGCCAAGUUCUCCACAUGUAAAUACUGUUAGAAGAGUUUUUAAAGAAAAAUUUAGUGUUUGCAAUUUUAACUCUCGUAUCUUCUGAUUUCUACGCCAAUGCUCUUAUCCUUAAAGCCACAUUUGUCCCUUGGCUGAAGAGUUGUGAAAGAUCAGGAGACUUUUAGAACCUAUCCAUAACCAGUGUUGGCAUUUGCAAUAUCCAUGAUUGAAACAAAAUAUUUUCAAACCAACUACUUUUACUAAACAUGCAAUGUGCUGGCCACUUCAACAGAUAACCGGGCUUUGAGGAGGUAUAGGUGUAUUUCAAGAAAUGUACUAUCUAGCUAGGAAGAGAGAAGGAUAGGUAAGACAACAGCAAUGGGGGAAAAACCACAAUAAUAUAUGACGAAUGUUAGAUGUGACUUUAAGAGUUCAGGGGGCGGCGGGGGUGUGGGGGCGGAGCCGGGCGCGGUGGCUCAAGCCUGUGAUCCCAGCACUUUGGGAGGCCGGGGCGGGCGGAUCACAAGGUCAGGAGAUCGAGACCAUCCUGGCUAACACGGUGAAACCCCGUCUCUACUAAACAAAAUACAAAAAAUUAGCCGGGCGUGAUGGCGGGCGCCUGUAGUCCCAGCUACUCGGGAGGCUAAGGCAGUAGAAUGGCGUGAACCCGGUAGGCGGAGGUUGCAGUGAGCCGAGAUCUUGCCAUUGCACUGCAGCCUGGGCGACAGAGCGAGACUCCGUCUCAAAAAAAAAAAAAAAAAAAAAAGAGUUCAGAGGAGGGUAACGGAGGGAAAUCGGAGGCUGUUUCAGAAGGUGCCCAGCAACAAGUGGGACUUAAGCCGGACUCCUGCAACAUCCGAGUAAAUAACAGAUGCGGGUGAAAGAUCCAACUAAAGCUUUACCUGAGAAAGCCAAAAGAAGUAAAAGGCCUACUGUACCUCAUGAUGAAGACUCUUCAGAUGAUAUUGCUGUAGGUUUAACUUGCCAACAUGUAAGUCAUGCUAUCAGCGUGAAUCAUGUAAAGAGAGCAAUAGCUGAGAAUCUGUGGUCAGUUUGCUCAGAAUGUUUAAAAGAAAGAAGAUUCUAUGAUGGGCAGCUAGUACUUACUUCUGAUAUUUGGUUGUGCCUCAAGUGUGGCUUCCAGGGAUGUGGUAAAAACUCAGAAAGCCAACAUUCAUUGAAGCACUUUAAGAGUUCCAGAACAGAGCCCCAUUGUAUUAUAAUUAAUCUGAGCACAUGGAUUAUAUGGUGUUAUGAAUGUGAUGAAAAAUUAUCAACGCAUUGUAAUAAGAAGGUUUUGGCUCAGAUAGUUGAUUUUCUCCAGAAACAUGCUUCUAAAACACAAACAAGUGCAUUUUCUAGAAUCAUGAAACUUUGUGAAGAAAAAUGUGAAACAGAUGAAAUACAGAAGGGAGGAAAAUGCAGAAAUUUAUCUGUAAGAGGAAUUACAAAUUUAGGAAAUACUUGCUUUUUUAAUGCAGUCAUGCAGAACUUGGCACAGACUUAUACUCUUACUGAUCUGAUGAAUGAGAUCAAAGAAAGUAGUACAAAACUCAAGAUUUUUCCUUCCUCAGACUCUCAGCUGGACCCAUUGGUGGUGGAACUUUCAAGGCCUGGACCACUGACCUCAGCCUUGUUCCUGUUUCUUCACAGCAUGAAGGAGACUGAAAAAGGACCACUUUCUCCUAAAGUUCUUUUUAAUCAGCUUUGUCAGAAGGCACCUCGAUUUAAAGAUUUCCAGCAACAGGACAGUCAGGAGCUUCUUCAUUAUCUUCUGGAUGCAGUGAGGACAGAAGAAACAAAGCGAAUACAAGCUAGCAUUCUAAAAGCAUUUAACAACCCAACUACUAAAACUGCUGAUGAUGAAACUAGAAAAAAAGUCAAAGCAUAUGGAAAAGAAGGUGUGAAAAUGAACUUCAUAGAUCGGAUCUUUAUUGGUGAAUUAACUAGCACGGUCAUGUGUGAAGAAUGUGCAAAUAUCUCCACGGUGAAAGAUCCAUUCAUUGAUAUUUCACUUCCUAUAAUAGAAGAAAGGGUUUCAAAACCUUUACUUUGGGGAAGAAUGAAUAAAUAUAGAAGUUUACGGGAGACAGAUCAUGAUCGAUACAGUGGCAAUGUUACUAUAGAAAAUAUUCAUCAACCUAGAGCUGCCAAGAAGCAUUCUUCAUCUAAAGAUAAGAGUCAACUAAUUCAUGACCGAAAAUGUAUUAGAAAAUUGUCAUCUGGAGAAACUGUCACAUACCAGAAAAAUGAAAACCUUGAAAUGAAUGGGGAUUCUUUAAUGUUUGCCAGCCUCAUGAAUUCUGAGUCACGUCUGAAUGAAAGCCCUACUGAUGACAGUGAAAAAGAAGCCAGCCAUUCUGAAAGCAAUGUUGAUGCUGACAGUGAGCCUUCAGAAUCUGAAAGUGCUUCAAAGCAGACUGGGCUGUUCAGAUCCAGUAGUGGAUCCGGUGUGCAGCCAGAUGGACCCCUUUACCCUCUGUCAGCAGGUAAACUGCUGUACACCAAGGAGACUGACAGUGGUGAUAAGGAAAUGGCAGAAGCUAUUUCUGAACUUCGUUUGAGCAGCACUGUAACUGGAGAUCAAGAUUUUGACAGAGAAAAUCAGCCACUAAAUAUUUCAAAUAAUUUAUGUUUUUUAGAGGGGAAGCAUUUGAGGUCUUAUAGUCCCCAAAAUGCUUUUCAGACCCUUUCUCAGAGCUAUAUAACUACUUCUAAAGAAUGUUCAAUUCAGUCCUGUCUCUACCAGUUUACAUCUAUGGAAUUACUAAUGGGGAAUAAUAAGCUUCUAUGUGAGAAUUGUACUAAAAACAAACAGAAGUACCAAGAAGAAACCAGUUUUGCAGAAAAGAAAGUAGAAGGAGUUUAUACUAAUGCCAGGAAGCAAUUGCUCAUUUCUGCUGUUCCAGCUGUCCUAAUUCUCCACCUGAAAAGAUUUCAUCAGGCUGGCUUGAGUCUUCGUAAAGUAAACAGACAUGUAGAUUUUCCACUUAUGCUCGAUUUAGCACCAUUCUGCUCUGCUACUUGUAAGAAUGCAAGUGUGGGAGAUAAAGUUCUCUACGGUCUCUAUGGCAUAGUGGAACAUAGUGGCUCGAUGAGAGAAGGCCACUACACUGCUUAUGUGAAAGUGAGAACACCCUCCAGGAAAUUAUCGGAACAUAACACUAAAAAGAAAAAUGUGCCUGGUUUGAAAGCGGCUGAUAAUGAAUCAGCAGGCCAGUGGGUCCAUGUUAGUGACACUUACUUACAGGUGGUUCCAGAAUCAAGAGCACUUAGUGCACAAGCCUACCUUCUUUUCUAUGAAAGAGUAUUAUAACUAUUAAUGGUAAUGAUUAUUUAGGUCAUUUGUUUUUGAAUGCCACAGUGAUAACUAUAAUAUAUAAUGUGCCUUUCUAGUCUUCCCUCUUCUGUAGGAAUAGCAUGUUCCUCAAAUGGUCCUGAACUUUUUCACCAUUUUGGUGAACCCUUUUAAAGUAAAUUUACUCAAUGCUUUAAAAUUCAUAGUCUUAAAAUAAAUGUGAAUUUUGUUUCCAGGUAUUUAUUCUGGGGUACAAAAACUUCCCAGAAUUUACAGUAGGAAAGGAAACCCCUUUAUGAUGUGGCUUAUUAUUACAAGCAUUCAGAAAUGAUGCUGGCUAAGUCAAAUCAUUCCUUGAGACAGUGAUUCCUAAAUGUAAUGCCACCUUCCUGAACUCUCACAUAUUCUAUAUCAUGGUUAUUUUAAAAAAUAUAUUUUUAGCCUUUUGUAACCUUAGUCUUGUUUUGAGCAAUCAUAUUCCGUGUUUUAUGUGCUUUUAUAUUUUUAUAAUAAAUAUUAAAGUAAAACUAUUAAAAAUUGUUUAUCCACGUACCACUUAACUUAAAAUCAUCUCAGGGCCAUCUAGUGGUAUAUAUGUGUACUACCAUUUAGGAAACUGCUAUAACACAUAAUUUCAUGAAGUAACACCUAAUACGGUGUAGUUCCCUGGUCAUAUUUUAUACAAUUCAACCAUAUAAAAGGGUGUCACUGUAAUUUCAGUAGUGUGGGUUUACAAAUAAUCUGCUGGUUAGCUUAUUACCUUGAGGUUUUGAAAAACUAGAAUUAUAUUGAGGCAUUUCAUAAACAUAUCUCUUGCACCCUCUUCAUGGUGGAGUUAAGGAUAACUUGCAGGUGGUUGGCCAAGGCCCAAUAUAGAUGAUUAUAACAUUUAGAAUUGGCAAUUAGAAGUUGAUAAUCCAUAUAGGACCAUAGGAUAGCUUUGAAAUAUAAAUUACCAAAUUAUAUUUGUAAAUGAUAGAGAAUUAUAUUCUUAACAGAAAAAUAUAUACUUUUUCUACUUCUUGUAAAUACUAAACACAGUUUUGGGGUUUUGAAAUCACUUUGUCUUCAGCAAGCAUCAUUAAUAAGUUCAGGUGAAUUUAGCUUUUAAUGGGGCAUUAAGCUGGCAUUUUUGAUUUUCUUUUUAAAUAAUAGCAAAAAUAUCAUUUUUCCCCUCUAGAAUACAAAUUAUUGAGCUGUCAAAACUUGGCAUGAAGAAUAUACUAUUACUUAGGCUUAAAUAUCAAAAGAUAAUGGCUACUUCAGUGUCAUAUUGUUGAAAUAGAAACAAAACUGCAUGGUUCAAGCAUCCUAAUCAUUAGUGCCAAUGAAUGAUAGUGCAGGCAAGUGCCAGGUAAAUGCCUAGUCCCACUUCAUUCUCCUCCUGGGAAGAAAGGAUAAGAAUAGUGGCUGCAGAUAAGGUAUGGAAAUAUUUAAUCAAGACUGUCUUAAACACAUAAGCAUAUAUAAUGUUAUCAAGGUUACCAGUGCUGCCUUUUGAUAUAUGGAUGAACAUAACUGUAAUUAAAGACGGUAAUAGUAUACAAAAUGCAGAGCUUAAAAAUGUCAUUGCAUAAAUUCUAUUUUUAAGAUGUUGAAAUGUUAGUAGUGUUUUUCUUGAUUUUUAACAGUGAAAUAAUCAAGAAAUAUAUCUUUAAGUUAAUCUGCAAAGUCAGGCUGUGUUCUGUAAAAGGUAUUUCACAGCAUUUUCUGUUUAACUGUAAUCUGUUAUCAUGGAGAUCUCAGUACCAGAGCAGUGAAUUUUUUGAAAAAUAUUGACUGUCUUUAUUCAAGUCAGCCAUCUUGGUAAGAGCAGUUUUCAUCCCCCCACUGCCCAAAUGUAAAUAUAGAUCACCUAAUUUUUCUUACAGAAAGAUACUGUUAAGAGGCAUGCACUUUUCAUCGGAUGGUCACUUGUUUCUUGUUUCAAAGACAAAUAUUUGGAUAGAUACCCAUACUUGCUAUGAGUCAGUCACAGUGCUGACACUAUUUUAACAUCAUUUAAAAUGGAAAGAUCUACAUAGAUUUUUGACAUUAUUCCAGAAGUAACAUGCAAGUAAGAUAUUUUUAUUGUCAUUUUCUUCAUGUUAAAGGAGCUACUUAUGAAACCUAUUUUUUUAUGGCCUAGAGUUUAUGAGUGCUUUUUCCUUGUCUUCUGAAAAUGGAAUAAAUUGGAUUUUUGAUACUUAAGAAUUUCCUAAAGAUAGCUUUUGUAACAGAGAAAGCAUGUUAAAUUACACAUGGGUCUACCUUAAAAUUUUUGUUAUUAUUUCCAAAGCACAUUUGCAGGGAUAGUAAAUGUAUAUAGUAGCAAGUCUACUAUAAUAACAGUAGUUUCUGGAUCACCUCAGGAAACAGUAUAAAUAAAUAAUAAUGUUUACUUAUCAUCAACAUAACUACCAUAGUGUUUGAAUGAAUUAAAGUUUCAUUAGCUUUAUUUAGAAACUGGUUUACCCCAGCUUCCCGUUUUUUUCCAAAUAUAAAAUGAUAAAAUAUUGAUUAUGUGCCAAUAUUGUCAUUUAAUGUUCUUAAAACUUGUGAAGACCACCUUUUUAGGUAGCUGAGAAGAGUGAUAGUUGGUAUCAAUUUGUUAGCCAGGCAUGGUGGCUCAUGCUGUUGGGAGGCUGAGUGGGGAAGAUGCUUGAGCCCAGGAGGUCAAGGUGCAGUGAACCAUGAUCACACCACUGCAUUCCUGCAGAGUGACGGAGUGAGACCCUGUCUCAAAAAUAAAUAAAAAGAAGACAGUUGGUAUCAAUUCAAAGAAUAGUUGAUGCCUGUUCUCUUAUUUUAAAUGUACCAACAGAGCUAUUUUACUGUAUUUAAUAGUUCUUAGCUUCCAUGUGUGAUGAUUUUAAUCAGUGAUUUUAUGCAAUAGCUGAAGAAAAUUUUCUGAAGAUUAAGCUGUGAAAUGUAUCAACCCUCAUCUAAUUUUUGUAGUACAAAAUGACAUCCUGAUUCCUUUUAAAAAUUCACGUUUGUAAUUUAUUUUUCUGCAUGUAUUGAUCAAAUAAGCCUAAACCAAAUAUGUGCAAUAAAAUUGAGCCUUUAGAUAGUAUCUAGUGCAUUGUUAAAAAAGAUUAUUUCUAGAUAUUUAUGAUGUUUUUGUUUACGUAGAAAUCAUGAAUUCAAAUGUUUAAAAGAUGACCAUAUUUUCAAUUUUGAGUAAUACAUAUUAUUCCUACUGUUUUUUUUCUUUUGCCAUGUUUCUAGAAAACAGCUGUGUAACUUAUUGAGCGUUAUUUUGGUGUUACUGUAUAAAACAUGCAUAAUAAAUAUUCUUAUUUAUCUCAUGUUACAAGAUUGGUCCUGGAAUUUUCACAGUUUACGUUAUUGACAGAAUGUUUUAUCAACAAUGCAUUUGCUUAUGUCUUAGUCCACUCAGGCUGCUAUAAUAAAAUACCAUCAACUA